CUUCGGACAAGUGGGUCAUUUGGACUACUGGAGUUGCUGCUUUUGAAUCUUUUCUAGAAGAGAAAGAAGAAAAGGUUGUAAUACAGCUCAGGCAGUGAUUAUUAUAUUCCAGAGUAUAAAGAACCCAGAACUGAUUUGGCGAAUUUUCCCCUUGAUCACCACCUAUAAGGCAAAUUAUCCAGGAUGGUGUGGGAAAACCAGACCUUCAACUCCAUCUUCAUCCUGCUGGGAAUCUUCAAUCACAGUCCCACCCACACCUUCCUUUUUUCUCUGGUCCUGGGCAUCUUCUCACUGGCAUUGAUGGAAAAUAUUUCCAUGGUUCUCCUCAUCUACAUAGAGAAACAGCUCCACACCCCCAUGUACUUCCUCCUCAGUCAACUGUCCCUUAUGGACCUCAUGCUCAUCUGCACCACUCUACCCAAGAUGAUCUUCAGCUACUUGUCUGGGAAGAAAUCUAUCUCUCUGGCAGGUUGUGGAACUCAGAUAUUCUUCUAUGUGUCCCUGCUUGGAGCUGAAUGUUUCUUGUUGGCUGUCAUGGCUUAUGACCGCUAUGUGGCUAUAUGUCACCCUCUUCAGUACACCAUCCUCAUGAAUCCGAAACUCUGUGUCUUCAUGACUGUUGCUUCCUGGACCUUGGGGUCUCUUGAUGGGAUCAUAGUGCUUGCAGCUGUCCUGUCAUUUUCUUACUGCAGCUCUCUGGAAAUUCAUCACUUUUUCUGUGAUGUUGCUGCCCUUUUACCUCUAUCCUGCACAGAAACAUCUGCAUUUGAAAGACUACUUGUCAUUUGUUGUGUGGUAAUGCUAAUCUUUCCAGUUUCAGUUAUCAUACUUUCCUAUUCCCAUGUCCUUCGAGCCGUCAUCCACAUGGGCUCUGGGGAAAGUCGUCGCAAGGCCUUCACUACCUGCUCCUCCCACCUGUCUGUGGUCGGACUCUACUACGGUGCUGCUAUGUUCAUGUACAUGAGACCAGCUUCUAAACAUACGCCAGACCAGGACAAGAUGGUGUCGGCCUUCUACACUAUUCUCACCCCUAUGCUGAACCCUCUCAUUUAUAGCCUCCGCAACAAAGAAGUGUUCAGGGCACUACAGAAGGUACUGAAGAAAAGAAAGUUAAUAUGACCUUAUCAAAAUCUUUUUGAGUGCCUACUGUGGUCAACACUCAUUCAAAAAAACUGGAAUCUCUUAAAUUAUUCUAUUUCUAUUUCUGGUAAUUUGUAUUAAUAUUUUCCACUUCUUUUCAAAAUUAUCUAUUCAGUAUAUUAUUACAUAUACAUCGUUUGUAUACUAAGCUAGAUUUGGAUGUUAGUAUAAGUGGUUUAAUCCCUGUGAAUGACAAUUAUAUUAUUAGGUGUCACACAUGGGUGGUACUUGAUUUUAGGAUGCUUACUUUUGAAGCCAGGUAUAAGUCCGAAGGGUCUUAGCUGUAUCAAAAAGCAAAGGUUGGAGUUGAUCCUCUGUUUUUGGAGAGAUGCUUCUUUGUUCACAAAUUACUUACCUAUUAGUACUUGUUUUUAAUUUGCCCAUCCUCAAACCCAAGAAUGACUAUUUUAAUACUGAUUCUUCUUUACUUGACUCCCAAGUAUUUAAAAGUGCGGAGUUAGUAUCAACACUUUCUUCAAUCAAGUUUUAUGUCUGCAUAAAAUAUUUCCUAGAAACUCGUAUAAACAUACACACACUUAAGUAUAUAUGUGUGUGAUCUUUAUGCUAAUAAAAUUAAAUAUUUUAAGGAGUCCACAUAAAAUAUCUAUUUGGGCUGCACAGUCAACAUCUGUAUCAUGUCUGCUUUUAUUCCUUAUAAUCCUUAUAUUAACCAUCAGAAUCUGAAGGCAGAGCAAGAUGAUGGAAUAGAAGGCUCCACUGAUCGUUCACAUGCAAGGACAGCAAUUUAACAAUAAUCCAUACACGAACAACACAUUCAUGAGAGCCAAAAAUCAGGUGAGCCUUCGUAGUACCUGGUUUUAACUUUAUAUCACUGAAGAGGCAGUGAAGAGGUAGAAAAAACAACUUGAACAGACAAUGCCACCCCUCUCUCACCACUGACAGAAGGAACAGUGUGCUAAGAGUGUCUCUGGGCUCUGGUGAGAAAGAACACAGCAAUUGUGAGGCUUUGAGCUCAGUGCUGUCCUGUAAGAGCAGAAAGGAAAACCAGAUAAAAUUCAGCUGAUGCCUGGCCACAGACAGAGCAUUUAAACCAGCCCUUGUCAGAGGGGAAUUACUGAUCCCAGUGGUCAAAACUUGUGUUCCCACAAACCUUGACACUGAGGGCUAAAAUGCGCUGAGGCUCUAAGUAAACUUAAAAGGCGGUCUAUGCCAUAAGUACUGCAACUCUUAGGUGAGUCCUAGUGCUGAAUUGGGCCCCGAGAUAGUGGACUGUGCGGCGGGCACGUGAACUACAGAGACAGCAGCUGGGGCAACUGAGGUUGUGCUGGCAUCACCCUUGCCUAACCUCAGGCUGCACAGCUCAUGGCUCCAAAAGAGUUCUUCCACUUGAGGAGAAGAAAGAGUGGAGAGGACUUUGUCUCACAUCUUGGAUACCAGUUUAGCCACAGCAAGAAAAUGCACUCGUCAAAGCUGUGAGGCCCUUAUUCCAGGACCUCCAUCCCAGAUGACAUUUCUAUAUACACCCUGGGCAAGAAGGGACUAACACUGUUGCUUAAUAUUUUGCUUCGUAAGCACCAAUGGAUUGAUUCAACUGAAAUUUUUGUACUCACCACAGUAAUAUUCAUAAUUAUUAUUUAGAUUGACAUGCUUAUUUUUAAGUAUAGUAUAAUCAAAUGUUUUCUAAUUUAAAAAUGUGCUAGCAAAUUUUAAAAAUUAAAACAAAGGCUAAUUUUAUCCUUAAAAAAAAUAAUUUCUGGGCCGGAUGCAGUGGCUCGCUCAUGCCUGUAAUCCCAGCACUUUGGGAGGCCGAGGCGGGCAGAUUAUCUGAGGUUGGGAGUUCAAGGCCAGCCUGACCAACAUGGAGAAAUUUCAUCUCGACUAAAAAAAUACAAAAUCAGCCGGGCGUGGUGGCCCAUGCCUGUAAUCCCAGCUACUCGUGGGGCUGAGGCAGGAGAAUCGCUUGAACUUGGGAAGUGGAGGUUGCUGUGAGCCGAGAUCAUGCCAUUGCACUCCAGCCUGGGCAACAAAAGCAAAACUCCAUCUCAGUAAAUAAAUAAAUAAAUAAUUUCUGUUAAAUAUAAAAAGUAGUUUUUAUCAUAGCAAAUGUCGCCCUAGCUAUGUCAAGUCAAAAAUUUAGAUUUAUUGGGAUUUUAAAAGAAGAUAAUACUAUGUCCCUAUGUGUUUCAUUCCACUUUAUGAUACACACUGGAAAUGUUUAUGCUCAGUUUUUGGAAGCAGAAUAUAUGUGUCGUGGGUACAGUUGCUCAAUUUAUUCAAUUUAUACUUGUAUAUGCUGAUUCUUCACCAAUGAAUUCAAUUUUAUUAAUUCAAUUAAUUAAAUUUUAUAAUACAAAACAGUGAAUUUAAUGACAUAUCUUUGCCAGUCAGUGUUCACUGGUUGAGCCAGAAAGAGUUUUACAAAGUUUUUUUUUGAGACGGAGUCUUGCUCUGUCACCAGGCUGGAGUGCAAUGGUGGGAUCUUGGCUCACUGCAGCCUCCACCUCCUGGGUCCAAGUGAUUCUCCUGCCUCAGCCUCCCGAGUAGCCAGGACUACAGGCGCAUGCUACCACAACUGGCUAAUUUUUGUAUUUUUAGUAGAGACGGGAUUUCACCAUGUUGGCCAGGAUGGUCUCAAUCUCUUGACCUCGUGAUCCGCCCGCCUUGGCCUCCCAAAGUGCCUGGAUUACAUGCGUCAGCCACAGCACCCAGCCCCGAGUUUUACAAAGAUUUACUGUACUUUCACUCCCACUCCGGAUCUUCUUUAAUCAAAAUAUAUAGCAAGCAUUUCAAUAGUCAUGAUAACAAAUAGAAGUGUGAUUUACAUUUUGUCAGCAACAUCACACCUUAUGUGAAACAGGUAAAUUUAGAACAACCAGAAAAGAAAGACUUAUCUGUGAUCUACUAAGAGAAGUAUGAAAAUUGAGCUUGAAAUGGAAACAUUUUAUGAUAUGAAUCGAUAAUGAUUUUGUACAUUUGAUUUUACACAUAAUAUGCAGAAAAAAGUAAUUUUAAUAUGCAAUUAUGUAAACUGCAAAAUCUACAAGAAACAUUUGAAAACAAUUUUGAUAUUGAUGAAUUUAAAGUUACUUUUUAAUUUAUAUGUUAAAUUUUUGAAUUUGAUGUUAAUAAUACCGACUUGAAAGAAGUUAUAUUGCUUACUCAAUUUAGUGAUGAAAAAUGUUUUGAGUAUGUUUGGGACAUUGCGUAUAUGUGAAUCUAAUUUUUCAACUGUAAAUUUUAUUAAAUUUAAAUGCAGACCAAGUAUUUUUGAAAAAAAAUUAGUGUCUGAAUUAUGAGCUGAAAAUGUAAAAUAAACGCUUGAUUUUAAAAAGUUUAUACAUAAAAUGUAAAAUAUAUCGUUAUUAAUUUUUAAGGUUGCUUGCCUGUUGAAACAAUAUUUUGGACGUAUUAGUUUUAACUUAAUUUUUGGUGUUGAAGUUUGGGCUGUAAUCCAGUAGAUGGCGCCUAAGAGUAAUGCCCGUAGAGAGGCUCUUGAUCGGCCACUUGGCUCUUUCGUGUUUCCUGGCAUUCGCAGGCACGCUGUCCGGUGGGGGUUGAGAGAGAUGCCUCCUUACCAGGACGACUCCUGAGCCUUGGAGGAGGCCCCUCCAAUUACUAGCACUUCGCCUGCAUUUCUUUUAUUAGAUGUUUCGGGCUACAGCCCUCCCUCAGGCAGAGGCCACAGCAGAGAGAGCUACCUUUCAGCAUGUACAGAAAUUAACUCGAGAUGGAUUAAAGACUUAAACGUAAGAAAAUCCUAGAAGAAAACUUAGGAAAUGCCGUUCUUGAUACCAGGCUUGGCAAAUAAUUUUUGGCUAAUUUCCCAAAAACAUUUGCAACAAAAAUUGACAAGCUAGACCUAAUUAAAGAGCUUCUUCACAGCAACAGAAAUUAUCAGCAGAGUAAACAGACAAUCUACAGAAUGGGAGAAGAUAUUAGCAAAAUGUGCAUCCAACAAAGGUCUAACAUCCAGAUUCUAUACGGAACUUAAGUCAACAAGCAAAACCCCAUUAAAUAAUCCCAUUAAAAAGUGGGCAAAGCACAUGACCAUGCAUUUCUCAAAAGAAGGCAUAUGAGCAGCCAACAAACAUGAAAAAAUGGUCAUCAUAGUUAGUUAUGAGAGAAAUGCAAAUCAAAACCUAAAUGAGAGACCAUCUCACACCAGUCCCGUCAAAAUGACCAUUAAUAAAGUCAAAUAAUAACAAAUACUAGUGAAGCUGUGGAGAAAAGGAACACAUAUACACUGUUGGUGGGAAUGUAAAUUAUAGUUGAGCCACUGUGGAAAGCAGUUUGGAGAUUUCUCGAAGAACUUAAAACAGGGCUGCUACUUGACCCAGGAAUGCUAUUACUGGGGAUACAUCCAAAAGAAAAUAAAUUGUUCUACCCCAAAGACAAAUUAUUCAUUCAUUGCAGUGUUAUUCCCAAUAGCAAGGAAUCAACCUACAUGCCCAUCAAUGGUGGAUUGGAUAAAGAAAAUGUAGCACAUAAACACCACAGAGUGCUACAUAGCCAUAAAAAAGAACAAAAUCAUGUCCUUUGUAGCAACAUGGAUGCAACUGGAGGCCAUUAUCCUAAGUGAAUUAAUGCAGUAACAAAAAACCAAAUACUGCAUGUUCUCACUUAUACAUAGGAGCUAAACUUUGGGUACUCAAGGAUGUAAAGAUGGAAACAAUAGACACUGUGGACUACCAAAUGGGGAAGGAAGGGAGGGGAGUGUGGGUUGCAAAACUACCUAUGGGAUACUAUGCUCACAACCUGGGUGAUGGGAUCUAUACCCUAAACCUCAGCGUGAUGAAAUAUACACAUGUAACAAACACGCACAUGUACCCACUG